CCCUGGCCUCCCGCGAGCUGCGCACCGCCGGCCGCUGCCCCAGCUGCCCGAGCCCGCGCCCUCGUCCGCGCGACCCGGCGGGGGGCUCCAGGCCGGCAGCAUGAGCGGCGGCGGCGACGUGGUGUGCACCGGCUGGCUGAGGAAAUCGCCUCCCGAGAAGAAGUUGAGGCGCUAUGCCUGGAAGAAACGCUGGUUUAUCCUGCGGAGUGGCCGGAUGAGCGGUGACCCAGAUGUUCUGGAAUACUACAAGAACGAUCACUCCAAGAAGCCUCUGCGGAUCAUCAACCUGAACUUCUGUGAGCAGGUAGAUGCAGGCCUGACCUUUAACAAGAAGGAGCUGCAGGAUAGUUUUGUGUUUGACAUCAAGACCAGUGAACGCACCUUUUACCUGGUGGCUGAGACAGAAGAGGACAUGAAUAAGUGGGUCCAGAGCAUCUGCCAGAUCUGUGGCUUCAAUCAGGCUGAGGAGAGCACAGACUCCCUGAGAAAUGUUUCCUCAGCCGGUCAUGGCCCCCGCUCUUCUCCAGCUGAGCUCAGCAGCUCUAGCCAGCACCUUCUCCGAGAGCGCAAGUCCUCAGCCCCAUCACACUCCAGCCAGCCAACUCUGUUCACGUUUGAACCCCCUGUGUCAAACCACAUGCAGCCCACCUUGUCCACCAGCGCACCUCAGGAGUAUCUCUACUUGCACCAGUGCAUAAGCCGAAGAGCAGAAAAUGCAAGGAGUGCCAGCUUCUCUCAGGGCACCAGAGCCUCUUUUCUCAUGAGGAGUGACACAGCUGUACAAAAACUUGCCCAGGGCAAUGGACACUGUGUCAACGGGAUCAGUGGUCAAGUCCAUGGCUUCUAUAGCCUUCCCAAGCCGAGCCGGCACAAUACAGAAUUCAGAGACAGUACCUACGACCUCCCCCGCAGCCUGGCCUCCCAUGGCCACACCAAGGGCAGCCUCACAGGCUCCGAGACAGAUAAUGAGGAUGUGUACACCUUCAAGACGCCCAGCAACACCCUGUGCAGGGAGUUCGGGGACCUCCUGGUAGACAAUAUGGAUGUUCCGGCCACCCCACUCUCAGCCUACCAGAUCCCUAGGACAUUCACUCUGGACAAAAACCACAAUGCCAUGACAGUGGCCACUCCUGGGGACUCAGCCAUAGCUCCCCCACCCCGCCCCCCCAAGCCAAGUCAGGCAGAAACACCUCGAUGGGGCAGUCCUCAGCAGAGACCGCCAAUCAGUGAAAAUAGCAGAUCUGUCGCUGCCACCAUCCCCAGACGCAACACCCUCCCUGCAAUGGACAACAGCCGACUUCACCGAGCUUCUUCCUGUGAGACCUACGAGUACCCACAGCGUGGUGGAGAGAGUGCAGGCCGGUCUGCUGAAUCCAUGAGUGAUGGAGUUGGCUCUUUCCUGCCAGGGAAAAUGAUUGUGGGCCGAUCGGACAGCACCAAUUCUGAAGACAACUAUGUGCCCAUGAAUCCAGGUUCUUCCACCCUGUUGGCCAUGGAACGAGCAGGUGAUAAUUCCCAGAGCGUCUACAUCCCAAUGAGCCCAGGGGCCCAUCACUUUGACUCACUUGGCUACCCAUCAACAACCCUUCCUGUGCACCGAGGCCCCAGCAGAGGAAGUGAGAUUCAGCCACCCCCUGUCAACCGCAACCUCAAACCUGAUCGGAAAGCAAAGCCAACACCACUUGACCUGAGGAACAACACCGUCAUCGAUGAACUCCCCUUCAAGUCACCUAUCACCAAGUCUUGGUCUAGGGCCAACCACACCUUCAACUCCAGCUCCUCCCAGUACUGCCGCCCCAUCUCCACCCAGAGCAUCACCAGCACAGACUCAGGAGACAGCGAAGAGAACUAUGUCCCUAUGCAAAACCCAGUGUCUGCAUCUCCCGUUCCCAGUGGCACGAACAGUCCUGCCCCUAAGAAGAGCACCGGCAGCGUUGAUUAUCUGGCCCUGGACUUCCAGCCGAGCUCCCCAAGCCCCCACCGCAAGCCAUCUACUUCAUCCGUCACCUCUGAUGAGAAGGUGGACUACGUUCAGGUGGACAAGGAGAAGACCCAGGCCCUGCAGAACACCAUGCAGGAGUGGACAGACGUGCGGCAGUCCUCAGAGCCUUCCAAGGGUGCCAAGCUGUGAUGAGAGGGCCACCGCAGAGCCCAGGAGGCAGCAUCUCCAGAGCUGGCCCUUCCCAUCUCCCCUCUCCCCUCUCCCGUUCUUCCUCCCAUCCACCUCCUCUCUACUCUGCCAGUCUCAGCCUUCAAAGCACUUGACAUCAGGGACCCUGAACCCUUCCCCUGGGAGGUGAGGGCCUGAUCAAGGCACCUCCUCUGCCCACUCGGGGCCCAGCUGUGAUUUUUAUCAGUAAUGGCCAUGCCUCCACCCACCUUAGUUAGGAGCUACUUCCAAAAAGCAUCCUUCAGCCUCUUCCUGUCCUUUAGACCUGACUCUCUACCAGAUGUUUGGAGGGAAGGGCUGGGGCUCUGAGCCAGAUUCCACACCUCACGUUCAGUCACAGCCCUCAGCUAUCUUCCCUCCGGCCACUGGGCUACCUCUCCUUCAGUCCCAGAAGACAAGUCUCACCAACCCAGGGAGUCAAGGACCAGCAAACCAAAGUGGAUAAUGGACUUUUUCAUUCCUGUUUUUCUUGGCAGGAGAGAAGCAAGGCCACUAAAAGAGGAGAUGGUGGAGACGGAGGCUCAGCAGUGGUCUUGAGGGGUAAAGGACUUAGAUGCCCAGAUGAAGAGGGAAAGCUGACAUCUGCAGGGAACCCACUUUGAGGCUGAGGCCAUGGCAGGACAGCUGCUGUGGGGUGCAGAGGCAGAAGAUGAAGGACAAAAGGAAGGGAAAACUGAUGGCCAACCUAGAGCAGCAAGGAGCAGGGCUUGGAGCUCGGGUGGUGGAGAUGACAAGGACACUGUGGGGUCUGGGUCCCCAGAACUCUGGAGCUACAGGCCACUCUAGGCCCAAGGGCUAGUCCUCUUCCCCAGUCCCCUCAGAGGCCCCCGCCAGCCCCACCUUGAAAGCAGCAUACAGGGGAAGGCUUGGACCAAGCUGGGCGACCAAGCACAUGGGGCAGGAACACAUGGUAAAGGGGUGGGGAAUAUGGGAGGGAGUGUGGUGUGGAUGGGGGUGAUGCAGGGACUGAGGGGAACCCUGGGACAGGCACAGGCUGGGCAGAGGCACAGGGCAGUGCAGGGGACUCUGCAGUGGGGUCGGGAAGUGAGUUUCUUUGCAGUGAGCAGUGCAGUGGAAGUCGGGCACAGAGGUAGCAGACAGAUGUGAAGCAGUGGUGAAGGCCAUGUAGCAAGUGGGGAAAUACAUCCAAAGGGCCUGGGAGUUGGGGGGUGCCCAACGCAAUCCUUGGGGGUGCAGGGUGGAGCAGAAAGUGAAGGAGGGACACGUGCAAGAGUGGUGUGCAUGGUGGUGUGACAUGAGGACCGUUCCUAGGAUGGGACAGUGGGUCAGGCAGGACAAGGAGAAAGCAGGGCAGAAUGAUGCCUAGAGGACCACAUCAGGCAUGGCUGACAGCUUGUGCCCAUGGGCUGUGGCGUAUGUCAGAUCGCAGGGUAGGAACGAGUCUGGCCUGGUGCCGGCCCAGUGUUUCCUCAGCUCAUCCGCCCUCUGUUGCUCCCUAGCAUUCCAGGAGCCAUCUUGGACUCUCCUCCCCAGGUUUGAAAGGCCAUCAGAUUAGCAGGGACGGGGUGUAGGGCAUCACCCAAGGUUCCUUCUCUUAAACUAAGGGUGGGGGAUCUGAAUGUUUUUAUGUUGACUGUUCUUGACUAAAUUUUCAAGAGUUUCAGAAGCAACAGGACAGACCAGACGUUUCAUUCUACCCUGGGGCGAACAGAACUUCUUCCUCCCAAACAAUGACUUCCUGCCAUGUUUGAUGGGGACAGCUACCACUGUCCUCUGCCCCCAUUCCCCUUUCAGCUCCCAUGAGCAUGCAUAGUUCACCAGACCAAUGGCCUAGCCAUUCUCUAAGUCCCAUCCUGGAAGAAGUUAUUUCUUCAAGAGCUGCACCUCUCCUCCUAGCAUUAGUUUAGAUCAACUCAAGGAGUAUUUAUUAAUGGCUGCUGUCUCCAGUUUCUGGGGUUAAGCACUAAGGACACAAGAAUCAAUCAGACCUUCUCCCUGAACUUAAGAUAGCCACAAUCAGAAAAAGGACAAGGACAUGAGACAGUGGUGAUGGCCAUCAGACAGAGACUUCAAAUGCUGAUGGAGGGCAGAGGAAGUACUUAGGGAGGUUGGUGUCAGAGGCAGGAGUGGGGGAUCAGGGAAGGUGGAUUCUAGGAAAAGGGAGUGCCUGAGGUAGGCCUUAGAAGGGGAUGAGUCAGAUUUUUACAGAGGAGGAGGGCAGGGCUUGGGUCCAGUGGAGGAAGAAGGAAGGAGAGGCUUGGAAAGCCUUGUGUCUUGGGAACAAAAGGCCUUUGAGCAUAUGGGUCCAGCCACUCAGAAGUGUAGGGGCCAUGCCUUGGUGUUCCAAUAAGUGAAUGGAAGCAGUGGUGGUAGCUACACUGGGCAGAGUUGGCAGGGUGCUGGUUCACUCUGCCCAGCCCUGAAUGUGUGCCUUAAAGGCCCCCUACAAGGGGCCCCAUACGACAGAGCUUUUAACUGGUGCCUUCCCUGUACCCGCAGCAGCCACAAGUGGGCCCAGACUAUUGCAGCCUCCCAUAAACAUGUGAGCAUGUUCUGAGUGUGCCAUGAUGUGAGUGGACCUGGCUGGAAUCUUCGGAGAGCGACUGAGGUGUUCAAAUCGAAUCUCCCAGGAGGCUUCCUUCCAGCCCCCUAUUCUGGUAACUACCAGGAGGCUUCCUUCCAGCCCCCUAUUCUGGUAACUACCAAAAUCCCUCGGGUGCAAGUGUAGGGGUAGAGAUGGAAGGAUGAGAGGUGAAAUUGACCUUUUGAAAGCAAAGCUCUGGCUCACAGGCCCCAAACUACCAGCCGUAUCUAGCAUAUCCCCACCCUCCACCCACUACCUCCUCCAACAAAGGAGUCAACUCAGUUGAAAAAACUGGUCCUUUGGCCUAUCCAUGGGUCAAAGUCCACCUCUCCUGGGGGCCUGGAGAGGACUGAGCCUACGGAAAGGGGAUACCUUCCCACUCAGCACUGCUUCACACAGGCCCCCUGCCUGGGGCUCUCCAAGGAGCCUUCUUCACCCACUUCCAGCUCCACUUCUGCAAGGUUAAGUCAAGUGAGAACGAUGAGAAAUAGGGAGAUGGUGUCUCCUUAAGUCCUUGAUCUGCCUGUCUGUGGAAUGGGAGGUUGGAUUAGCUGCGCUGAGGUCCCAUCCACAGCUGGUGCUCAGCUGCUUGAAGGGGAGACUCCCUCCUCUGUAACUUCUUUCUGGGGGAUUGGGGUGGGCAGUACCUAUCCCCAGUCCCCUCCUAGCUUGACUUUAGUGGUUUCCAAUGUAGAAGUUAACAAAGUAUGCCCCAUUCCUGUGACAAAAGCACAACCAUUCUGAAGUUACUGGAGCAUGGGCUCAGCUCAUCCUCCCUCUGGCCCCUUCUCCCAUGGGGACAUCUCGGCCCAGCACCCCUAUCCCAUUUCCAGAGUUCUUCCUUCCCCAUCUGGGCCUUCAUAAAAUGCAGGGGAAGCCAGACUGGUCUCAGGAGCGCUAAAGCCCUUCCGUGGGGGGUCGUCUUUCUGGGACUAGCCCUGCUGUUUAGGACCUGGGACCACAAUGGGGUACCUGCCGAGGGGGUCCCCAAGAGAUCCAGGCUGUCAUGUGAUUUAUGGUGGCAUGUGUUGUGUAUUUGUUGGCUACUUGUGUCUUGAAAUCUAGAAUUAUUUCACGCAGAAUUGUCACUGUUUGUCAGGAAGAGAAAAUGGGCUAGUGGAAGCCCAGUCUUGAGUUCUUGUCUUGUUACCAUUUAAAAUUGACAUUUAAUUUUCAAAUCACUGUUGGUGCCUAAUCACUUAAGUUAUUAAUUUAUUCUGUUGUAUUCUUUUUUUUAAAUUGUAACAUAUUUAUCCGGUGGGUGGGACAGGAGUGUGUUCAAGUGGGUCAUGUUUUUGCUGUGGUGACACAUGGUACAGGCUUGGAGCUUGCAGGUCCCUUUCUACUGUGGUGUUGGAGCAGGACAAUAAAGUCCACUAGAAAUGCACCCCAGAA